AAACACUCCGACCUCAGCUGGUCCAGCAUGCUGGGCACCGUGCUGCUGCUGGCCCUGCUCCCAGGGAUCACCACCUUACCCAGCGGGCCACCUGGUAUGUAUGGGCAGGGAGGUGACGGGUCUGUCAUGCUUCUAUCCCUGUUUCACCCUCUUUAUUUUUUUUGAGAUGGAGUCUUGCUCUGCCACGCAGGCUGGAGUGCAGUGGCGCAAUCUCCACUCACCGCAACCUCCGCCUCCCCGGUUCAAGUGAUUCUCCUGCCUCAGCCUCCUGAGUAGCUGGGACUACAGGCACGCACCACCACGCCUGGCUAAUUGUUGUAUUUUUAGUAGAGACAGCGUUUCCCCAUGUUGGCCAGGCUGGUCUCGAACUCCUGACCUCAGGCGAUCCGCCCGCCUCGAACUUUUCAAAGUGCUGGGAUUACAGGUGUGAGCCACCGCGCCCCACCGAUGUCACUCUCUUUCAACUAGACCUUUGGUGGUGGUCCUCAUGGGGGUGGGGACAGGGCAGGGGAGUGGGGUGGGGUCUCUGUCCCCCAUCCCAAGGGUGGCUCACAUCCCCACUUCGGCAAAGCUCCCUGCAGCCACGGAGAGGGCCAGAGUUGUGGGAGGGGGCCAGUCUACCCAGGUGCUCUUCAGAAGUGGGUGUGGUGUGCGGAUGGACAAGGGGGCUCAUGCCUGUAAUCCCAGCACUUAAGAGAGGCUGAGGUGAGAGGAUCGCUUGAAGCCAGGAGUUCCAGACCAGCCUGGGCAACAUAGACCCCGUAUGGCCGUGGUAGCGAGUGGCUGUGGUCAUAGCUACUCGAGAGGCUGAAGCAGGAGGAUGGCUGGAGCCCAGGAGGUGGAGGCUGCAGUGAGCUGUAUUCGCACCACUGCACUCCAGCCUGGGCGACAGAGGGAGACCCUGUCUCAGAAAACAAGAAAAAUGGAUGUGCAGGCAAUCUUUCGUAUUUGGAGAUUAGCCGUUUUACCAGGACCCCGCUCAGCACCUGAAGGCAGACAUCAGCGUGUGUUUAGGGGCACGAAGAGGGGAGGGGUCCCAUGGCUGCCUCAGCCUGGACAAGUGGAAGCGUCUCAGAUCUUGGUGGCCUGGCUGGGCUUUGGCUGUGCCCAGGAGAGCCUCUUGGGAGGGUAUCCUCUUCACUUCCCUUCCUCGUUGGUGACAGCACCUAUCUCCCCUUAGAAAGGGGAGCCGCCUGUCCUGCUGCGUCCCCAAGAGCAGCCCUGGGGAAGGUGGGGGAGCUCUGACUUCACCCAGCCGGACCCCACCAUCGGGUGCUCCUCACCGCUUCUCUUCCGCCCCAGGGAGGGCUUCGCCAGCUUCGGAGGCUUCUCUAGGGGCGCAUGGCUCUGCAACCGGCUCAGUUGCUGGGCUGUGCGAGUCCCAGGGGUCGCCAGGGGGCACAUCACCGUCAGGGGGGAAAGUGGCGCGGAGCCCAUCAUGGGUGAAUCGGCCGCCGCAACCGCAUCCCUUUUCCAAAGGCGGCGGCGGGGGCGAGGUGGUCGGGUCACUUUUCCCGGAGGCCUAAAGGGCAGCGCGCGUUUUCUCUCCUUUGGGCCGCCCUUCCCCGCCCCGCCAGCUCCCCCGUUCCCCGCGGCGCCCGGCCCCUGGCUGCGCAGACCCCUCUUCAGCCUGAAGCUGUCCGACACAGAGGACGUCUUUCCUCGCCGCGCGGGGCCGCUCGAGGUCCCGGCCGACAGCCGCGUGUUCGUGCAGGUGGGGACCCCGGGGACACCAGGGGCGGAUGGGGGCCGGUGGGGACGGGCGAUCCCUGAUGGCGCCUCCGUCCCCCAGGCGGCCUUGGCCCGUCCCUCCCCGCGCUGGGGCCUGGCCCUGCACCGCUGCUCAGUGACGCCGUCCUCACGCCCGGCCCCGGGGCCCGCCCUGGCUCUGCUGCGUGAGGGCUGCCCCGCCGACACCUCUGUCGCCUUCCCGCCACCGCCGCCGCCGAGCCCGGGUGCCGCCCGCCCCGCGCGUUUCAGCUUCCGCCUGCGCCCGGUCUUCAACGCCUCGGUGCAGUUCCUGCACUGCCAGCUGAGCCGCUGCCGCCGCCUCCGGGGAGUCCGCCGGGCGCCUGCGCCUCUGACGCCGCCGCCGCCGCCGCCGCCAUCGCGGUGUCUGCCUCAGGACGAGGCGUGCGCCGACACUGGCAGUGGCAGCGCCGAGGGCCUGGCUGCUGACGGCCCCCACCUGCACACGCUGACGCAGCCUAUCGUGGUCACCGUGCCGCGGCCGCCCCCCAGUGAGCACGCAGUCCUCCUCCGCAUGGGGCCGUGGGGCGGCAGAGCGGGUGGGAAGGACGCCUGGGAGCUGGACCCAGUCUCAGCGUGGCACUUCCCACAGGGCCGCCCAAGAGUGUCCCCGGCCGUGCAGUGCGCCCUGAGCCUCCCGCGCCGGCCCCCGCGGCCCUGGAACCCGCGCCGGUGGUGGCGCUGGUGUUGGCAGCCUUCGUGCUGGGCGCCGCGCUGGCCGCCGGGCUGGGUCUCGUCUGUGCGCACUCAGCGCCCCACGCCCCUGGCCCGCCCGCGAGAGCCUCGCCCAGCGGUCCCCAGCCCAGGAGGUCCCAGUGAGGAAGGGAUGGUGCGCCCCCAACAUGGUCCGGAGAUACACCCAGCUACCAAUUCGGGACCAGGACCAACAGGACCGGACCCGCCUCCCUGGACCUCGGACCUGAUGAGGCCACGACCCCUGCGCUUCUCUCCUCCCCCUGUCCCUCCCACCUGUGCUCAAAAUAAACCUCUGGACUGACCGGCUAA